GUCCCCGCAGUGCUCCCGGACCCGGCGAGCCUUCGGGGCGCGCGUCGCUGGUGGUGGUUGAGGCUCUAGCGAUAAUAAAUGAUAGAGGAUACAAUGACUUUGCUGUCUCUGCUGGGUCGCAUCAUGCGCUACUUCUUGCUGAGACCCGAGACGCUUUUCCUGCUGUGCAUCAGCUUGGCUCUAUGGAGUUACUUCUUCCACACCGACGAGGUGAAGACCAUCGUGAAGUCCAGCCGGGACGCCGUGAAGAUGGUGAAGGGCAAGGUAGCCGAGAUCAUGCAGAACGAUCGACUCGGGGGGCUUGAUGUGCUCGAGGCCGAGUUUUCCAAGACCUGGGAGUUCAAGAACCACAACGUGGCGGUGUACUCCAUCCAGGGCCGGAGAGACCACAUGGAGGACCGCUUCGAAGUUCUCACGGAUCUGGCCAACAAGACGCACCCGUCCAUCUUCGGGAUCUUCGACGGGCACGGGGGAGAGACUGCAGCUGAAUAUGUAAAAUCUCGACUCCCAGAGGCCCUUAAACAGCAUCUUCAGGACUACGAGAAAGACAAAGAAAAUAGUGUAUUAUCUUACCAGACCAUCCUUGAACAGCAGAUUUUGUCAAUUGACCGAGAAAUGCUAGAAAAAUUGACUGUAUCCUAUGAUGAAGCAGGCACAACGUGUUUGAUUGCUCUGCUAUCAGAUAAAGACCUCACUGUGGCCAACGUGGGUGACUCGCGCGGGGUCCUGUGUGACAAAGAUGGGAACGCUAUUCCUUUGUCUCAUGAUCACAAGCCUUACCAGUUGAAGGAAAGAAAGAGGAUAAAGAGAGCAGGUGGUUUCAUCAGUUUCAAUGGCUCCUGGAGGGUCCAGGGAAUCCUGGCCAUGUCUCGGUCCCUGGGGGAUUAUCCGCUGAAAAAUCUCAACGUGGUCAUCCCAGACCCAGACAUCCUGACCUUUGACCUGGACAAGCUUCAGCCUGAGUUCAUGAUCUUGGCAUCAGAUGGUCUCUGGGAUGCUUUCAGCAAUGAAGAAGCAGUUCGAUUCAUCAAGGAGCGCUUGGAUGAACCUCACUUUGGGGCCAAGAGCAUAGUUUUACAGUCAUUUUACAGAGGCUGCCCUGACAAUAUAACAGUCAUGGUGGUGAAGUUCAGAAAUAGCAGCAAAACAGAAGAGCAGUGAACCCUUCAGGGGUCUCAGCUGCCUUAGACUAAAGGACUUUCAACACACUGGUCUCUUUUAAUUUAGUGAAAAGUGUGGGAGUUGUAAUUAGGAUCAUCCACCCCAGACAUGGAAUCCCCCCUCCCUGGUGGUCUUAGGUCUAUAAUCAGUGACGAACAGAGGGUGCCCUUGGCCAAUGUAGUUAAGAAACUGGAAAAUGGUUUCUUCAUGUUUUCCCAACUCUUUCAUCCAGUGUCCAAAAUAUAUAAGUAAAUAGCUGUAGAGUCACAUAUAUGAAGUGAAUAGCAUAUGUGUCAUUUAGUCUCCCUGAAGAUUCUUUUCAAGAUCCUGUUCAGGGUCCUCCAGGCAUCAGCUGUUGUGUCCUCUCUUUGUAACAGUGGACAGGACAGACCACCCAGUGCUGCAGGAGACAGGCCACUGCGUCACCUGUGAGUGGUCAGGGGCUGAUGUGGCAACACCCUCUGCCAAGAGACAGAGCUGUCCUGAGAAUGCUUUGUCCUUCUGAGCCCAUGUUUUCUGCUCAGUAGCAGCUUGGAAGCAGAUUUGGAAUGGUUUACUAUUUUGGCUGCUCUUGGGGACUGCGAGAAGCAGAGAGAAUGAGAGACCAGUGGCAACUGCCUGCACAGCAGAGAUAACCCUCUUCCCUUGCUUCCUUUAAUAGUUAAAUAGACUUUGUAUACCACCUGACCAGCCUUUGUGCAUUUAUCCUAAUCAUGCAUGACCGUUAACCUUUUGCUUAGUCCUUACCAUAUGUAAUAGGCAGCUGUUAAAUUCACCAACAGAUACCCUGAUUUUUCAUCUUACGUGACCAAGAAACCACGUUAGGGGAAAUGAAAAAAGCAAGCCACAAUACCAUGAUUCCUUCCAUUUUCAACAGUAGAUGAAGGAAAUGAUACUGAAUGAGUCACAGUGUUCCCUGGCAAGUAAGCUGUUUGCAUUGAGAAAGGAGUGAGCUGGUGAGGUUACCACCCUGAAUUGAGCUCCAGCUGCCAGUUUUUGUGUUUUUCCUUGCCCCUUUCCAAGUGGUUUUCAAGUGUCAGGCAGUGUUCUGAGAAGCAGCAGCCUAUAACUGUAUGUGUGUUCCUUGAAGCCAGGUGCAGAGUUCCCAGCUACUGCAGCUUGGGAUUUGGUGGGAAACUACUGGGAUAAGCUUCUCCUUGACAAUGGAAAGGCAGCAGUCUUCAACAUUUGGUUGCAAAUCUCCAUCCACAUCAGGGAGCUUUCCCCAGGCAAAUACAAACCGCCCCGUGGCCUGCAGGCCUGCAGGGGAGGCAGCAAAGGGACCUGGCAGUUGCAACACAGUAAGUCAGGAAUUCAAGCGUGAACCCAUAUUGAUAAGUGGGCCAGAAUUAUUUAGGGGCCUGGCUUGCUGCUCUCCAUUUCCUGUAUCGCUAAUUUAUCAUUUUUCCAACCUUGGUAUUUUAUAUUAUUUAGAGAAAAUGCUGGGUCACUCUCUUUGCCUAAGGUGACUCAAACAGCCAAACGAAACUUCCGUUGCCUCCCAGCCCUCUGUAUCCACCUGGUUUUGUUCUUUCCCUGUGAGCAUUUGUGGUUAUAGCUUCCCAUAUGCCACAUUCACCGGCCACCUCCUCGCCGUGGAACCCUGCCCUCUCCCCUCCUGCUGCUGUAGAGUUUUCCCAAAGCAGUGUCCAGGAGAGAAUUUGAGAGAGUGAAGAAAUUGCCUUGUAGAUGUGGAGGGCUGCAAUCUGUCUUGAUUUCUCCAAGCACUUAACUUUCUUUGACUGCACUGAGAAUUGCUAAUGAUUUCCCAUGAGAUUUGCUUACUUUUGUAUACUGUAUUUUCCAGCAUUACAGAACCUUGGUUAUUGUUUUUUAGCCAUAGAAUCUUCUAGUAAAAAAUAUCUGCCACCAUUUUAGAUUUAAGCAUUUGCCUAUGGGGAGACACUGAAUAUGUGGAUGUGUGUAUUAAUAUUUGGGGUGGGGACAGGGAAGGGAAUGUGGAAAACAAAUGCUGGCUGUGAGCAGUGCUGAGAUGGCCAGGCCAGGCGGCUGAGUUUGCUUGGAAAUUCAGGACAUUCUGACUCCUAAGAGUUGCCCCCACCCACCAUCAAACUGAAAUCAGCACCAAUGGUGUCAGCACUUUACAGCCCAUAGCCAACUUUCUUUAUUUUUAACGUAGCACAAAAAUGUAUAAUAGCAAGGAAAAGACAUUUUUAAAUUCCGGUUAUUUUUAUUGUCUAAAAUGAAAGCAACAGUGUUUUGAUAAAGAUGAAAAAGAAAAGCUACUAAAUUAGUAAAUCAGUGGUUACGUGCCCUGCAGAAUUUCUUAACAGAUGGUGCUGAGUGCACGAGUUACAUAACUUUCUCUCUAAUUGAGGUUCACAAGGCGUCUUCUAAAUUUUGCUUUGUACAAUUAAUUCAUUUCUGAUGUUAACCAAAUAGAGUGUAUAUAUCCUACUCCCAUUACUGCCUCUUUCCCCCCUACUAUGGCUUGUAGAUUUUCAAAAGAUAGAAGUUCUAGGCAAAACUGUAGCAGUUUCAUUAAUAGUUGUUAGGAUAGUUAUAUCUAAAAUCAGAGUAUUUUGUUCCCUUCCUUCUGGAGCUCUCUCUCCCUAGCCCUUUUCCAGCUGUUGGGGAUGUGCAGACAUCACUCCUGGGGGUGCCCUAUGGUACACUGGCUGCUCCCCAGGGACCUGGGAAUGCUGAAUCUAGCCAUUAGGGAAAUUGAUUUGAGAUGUUUGCAUGUGAAGCUUCCCUAAGCAGCACUGCCAAAGCUUUGGAAUUGUCACCCAAGGCUUCCUAGACUCCCUAGCUAGCUCGAGUUCGAAUUGCCAAUAGUCCCCAUGGUGCCAAAUUUUGGGAUGGUUUUACAGUCUUUUAGAAAUGAAGACAGGAAUGGCCAUGUGCUUCUGAGACCCCAGCACGAUGCCAGGCCCAGGUCUCCAUUAAUGCAGUGCUCUGCUGCUGCUCCACUGGCAAUUUGUACUCUUAACAUAGGUUGGGGGAGGGACAGCUAGGGAAAUUUUUUUUAAUUAAUUGUAUCUAAAAUUCUUUCAUCAUAGGAAUAAACAACACAUAUAGAAAGCUCCAAAGCUGUUCCCAAGACCUGUAUUAUUUAUUUUAUAUGACCAACUUGCCCCAAGGCAAUUAACUCUGAAUUGCUGUUCUAAUGUGACAUAUCUGUGUACAUAUGUACAUAGUACUGGUAACCAGUGGCUGCAUUUUAUUCCUUGCUGUGGACUGAGGUAUUGGCUUCUUGAAUCUUGUAUAUGUCAUAAGAAUAUUAUACAGAGAGUGUUAUAGUGAAGGAUGUAAGCUGGAUAAUUUAAAACAGACCUUAUUUCAUACAAGUGUAAUUAUUACAUCAUUUUGGGUAAAUGGCAAACAGGAUUGCAUGAGAGUGAUGGCAUCAUCAUUUCAAUUGAAUCUGAAGUGAUUCUAGGAAAUUGAUUCCACUGUUGGAUUCUAGGAAAUUGAGUCCACUGUUUUCCUUUGCGUUUAAUUUCCUUUGUGUUUAAUUUGACCACAGAAACUUUUUUGAGUAGCACCUAGUAACAUUGCAAGGAACUUGUGUAUCAAGGUGUAUCUUGAUUAUCCUGAUUUUUUUUGUUCUCUAAGUUGUUGCCAGAUCUCUCUUGCAACUGUGUCAAUGAAAGGUCUGUGUUUAGAAAAGGCAGCAUAUCAUUGUAUAUUUGAAACUAUAGGAAUAUAUACUUUGUAUAAAACUUUUCCAAUGAUUUCAGAAAUUCUUUUUUCCUCCUUUUGACCCACAACUAGACUGUUCAUACCCUAAUAGUUCCCCAAAAUUGCCUUAGCAUGUCACACCAGCAUUUGUCAUCCAGCUCUGGAGAAAUGACAUGACUGUUAGAUACUAUGCCUGUUUAAUUGCCUCUGGAUUAAGUCAUUGAUAGCUAGACUUUUGAGCUAGUUAGCUGUAGAAAUAAUAGAAUCCAGUGUUUCCCAAAGUGUGUUCCAAAGAACACAAGUUCCAAAGAUGCUCUUCUAAAUAUAGGAUUCUAGGAUGAAAUAAGUUUGGAAAACACAUACCAUCUUAGAAAGUUAGUGAACAUGAGCACAUCAAAGGCUCUAAUUUAAAUGUCCUGUGAGGAGAGAAAAACACAACAAAUAUCUACUGUCAGUUAGCCCAGUGUUUUCCAGAUUAAUUUGACCACAGAAACUUUUUUGAGUGGCACCUAGUAACACUGCAAGGAACUUGUGUUCUAAAGAACACCCUUUGGGAAAUUCUGGUAUAUUGAAAUAUUGCUGUGUUUUCAUUCACGAUGACUCUUAGUAGCAGUACAAUUUGCAACUUAGAAGCAUGAGCCUUUCAUAUAUGAAGCUGACUUGUUAAUAAAAGCAGUGUUAAGAAGUAGUAUGACUUAAUAUGACCAACAGCAGCCUCAUAUUGAUAGCAGAACAAUCCUACUUAAAGCUCUAAACAUCAUCCCCCCCUUUUUUUUUUUAACGGAAUCUCGCUCUGUCACCCAGGCUGGAAUGCCGUGGCGCAAUGUCAGGUCACUGCAAGCUCCGCCUCCCAGGUUCACACCAUUCUCCUGCCUCAGCCUCCUGAGCAGCUGGGACUACAGGCGGCCUCCACCACACCUGGCUAAUUUUUUGUAUUUUUAGUAGAGACGGGGUUUCACCAUGUUAGCCAGGAUGGUCUUGAUAUCCUGACCUUGUAAUCCACCAGCCUUGGCCUCCCAAAGUGCUGGGAUUACAGGUGUGAGCCACUGCACCCGGCCAUCCCUUUCUUUUAUAUGAAUAAUGAGCAAGAGCCCUGCCAUAGCUAAAUAUGUCUCAAAUUCAUUCCAAGAUCUUUCCAUUGCUUUUUUGCAGUUACCUUUGCUUUUUGGGUUGAAUCAAAAUGAAUAUUUUUAUAUUUCAUUACUAUAUGAUAUUUAAAAAUAUACAGAAAAUCACAGAAAAGGAAAAACAGAAAUUUGAUUUUAAUUCACUUUUGAAAUUUUAACGAUUUUUAAAACUAAUGAUCUGUUAUAUAAUAACUGAAAUGUAAACUAUUAACAGUUAUUUACUUUCUUUCCUUUAUUGUCCUCUCUGGAUUCAGUGAAAUAAUUUGAAAUCAAUUAGAGCUCAUACCUUCUAAAACUCCUGUCCCAUAUCAUCCCACCUUUCAUGUUUUAUGUACAUAGUUAAGUUUGGCAUGUUAUCUCUUGCCUAAAAUGUGAGGCCUUCCUGUAGUUCCACAGUAGUUACUCUUGGCUGCAGAAAUAGGUUUGGGAAGCUAUGAGAGAUUACCCCAAAGUCAUGGAUGAAACAAAUCUAGUCGAAAACAUGGUACAGAGUGAAUUAAGGCAAAAGUCAUUAACUUAAAAUUACAUCCAAUAUUUAGGAAUAGCUCAUCCUCUGCACAUUAUCCAAAAUAUUUUAAAAAACUAAAAGUAAGAUCUCUUAGGCUAGGUGGCGGAUUGCAAAGGGCAGGGGGCAGUUGAUACCAUGAAGCUUCCAAUAGAUGCAUUUCUAAACAUUUUUUCUAAUAUGUAAAUUUGCUGAUCCUUAGUAAUGUUAAUGCUUUGUCUAUUUGUUAUUUUUACCACUGUUGAACAGCAAACUGUUGAGGCUAGGGUUGAUUAUUGAUAAUUUUUAUGUGUUUAGUAAUAACCACAGCAUCAUACGUACAACUGCUUUAAUAAAUCCAAGUUAAGGACUUUGAGGAGAGCAUGUAGCAAGUAUUCAUUUUAACAAAUCAUCACAGACAGUUUCCCUGUUCAAAGCUCCACCAAAAAGCAAGCAUGCAGCAAAGGCAUAGACUGUAUUUAGAGAUGUGGUUUCAUUUAUUCUUGAAGUCCUAUAACCUUGCAUUAUUUAAACACAAAAUCCCACCUAACAUUUGCCAAAUCCAAGUUAAUCUCAAAAACCUCCGAGGACAUUGAGCACAAGCAGAUUACUGUAAGGGCACUGGUGGCAGAUUGUGGUGGAGAGAGGGCUGAGUGACCCAGAGCAAAGCCUGCCCGGGUUACUCGCUGCCACUUCAGGAGAGGGAUUGUAUCAGCUCUCAUUACCUUUUGUCAUGAGGCAGUUCAUAAAUUAAAUAUGAUAUCAUGCAUUAUCUCAAAAUAUUUCUAUAUUAAUUAGAUAAUUCACGAUGUAAAACGUGUUCAUGCAGAAGCAAAGGCGGAUGUAAUAGUCAAGUAUCAGGGAAAAACCCCUUUAGGAUACCCAGACAUUAAAAAUGUAAAAAGUAGCUUAUAAGAAAUGUGGAUUAUCAGAUUUUUACUAUAUAUAGGUUGUGUUUAAUAGUAAUUUCUGACACCUGCACAUAGAUGAAGAAAAGGCAGUUGUUACCACUUUUCACCAUUCAAAAAAUGGGCUUGUCUCUUAGAGUAUUGGUUAAUGCUUUGCUUAUUUGUUAAUGAAGACAGCAUUUUAAUUUUAAAGCUUCCUUUUGUAGGACUGAUGGCACGGGCAGAAUCACAUUUAAGAAAAAUGGUUUGGAACACUUUUUAAUAAAAAAUUGUAAAAUCAGUUUCCAGUGUGGUCAAAAUUAGAAUGUAAAGGAAAGCAUUUUUAAGAAAAUACAGAAGCCCAAAUCAAGGGAGAGUAAUAUAAAAGGAAAUAUUUUAAAUUAAGAAAAGGAGGUGUUAUAGUUUAUUACAUCAUGAAUUAUGCUUUCUGUACUUACGCUCUUAGUGAAGGAGAUAACAUUGAAGUGAGAAAAUGAACAUUCUCAGUUAUUUGCGAAGUUAGUAAAAUUGCAGUCCCUAUUCCAUUUUUUUCUGAUGAAAAUGGAUACAUGAGAUCUCAUUUAUUGCUCUCCUCAACACCUUUACUGUCCCAGAUUCCAUUCACGUUCCAAAUCGUGGACAGUAAAACUGAAGUCAGAUAAACACAGUCACAGGUACAACUGGGAGCGAGUUUUAACAUAGUGGUAAUUUUGCAAAUGCCAACAUGAAUACUAGUGAGUACUCAAUUUACGACAGACAAUUUCACAAAAACCAACCACAGAGUGAUUUGAUAUUCUUGCUUCUUAGAGAGUUUUCUAAUCCAUAUAAUGCAAUGGGUCAGGUUGCUCAUAUGAUUAAAAAAAUUAAUCCUGUAGAAAUGAUGUAUUAGACAUCUCUAACCCAAGAAAAAGAUGUCUUUUGUAUAACUUUUAAAUUCCCAUUUGUCUAUCUUAGGACAAAUGAUGACUUCUUCGUGUAGUAAUGAAAACGUCUAAAUCCUGCUCUGUGGAGAAAAGCUAGAACCAUGGGACAUUAAGCAAGAAUACUCCUCUGAUUUAGGCUCCCAGACUACAACUAACAGUCUUUAUGUAUUUAUCAUCUUGGUUAUUGUUUUAUCUCAAGCAUAUACAGUGUGCAGAAAGUAGAAUAAUGAAUAAAAUAUGACCAUGGAGAAAACCCAUAACUUUUGCUUCUAUUAUAGAAAGCAGUGUUUGUUCUUUUUAAUUUAUUACAUGUUCACAUUGAAACAUUAACAUCUACAAUAUUGUCUUUCAGUUUACUCUUCAAUUACUAAAGCAAAUGAUUUUGAUUUAUAGCACUUACACAACUGCAGUUCAGGUCACAGAAUUGAAAUCUAUUUGAUAAUGUCUCAGCAUUCUCAUGGGCAGCCAGGAAAAAAAAAAAGAGAGAGAAAGACAAAUAGAAAUUUUAGUGGGUUCAGAUAAAUGAUUAUUCUGACAAACCUGGAAAAUAGUAAUUAAACAGUUCAUUCCAAAAGACCCCAAUGUAAACUCUGCUCACAUACAUAAUUUGUAUAAGGAAAAUGUAUGAGUUUUUUUCUUAAAAAUAAAUAGAAGCAUCAUUGCAUUUAUAACAGAUUGAUCAAUCUUAUGAACAGAUUACAUUGGGAAAGUCACUAUUAUUGCUGUGUGUUUGUAUAUUUUAUUCUUUCCUUUUUUGUGUGAGCAUCUACUAUGUGCCAGGCAGUGACUGUGUCUGAGUGAAUGUAUCCAUGGUGAGCACUCAGGCGCCAUCACUGCCUUCUUGGGGCUUACACCCUAUUGGGGUGUCAGAGAUAUUAUAACACUCAAUAUUGACCCAAUGGGAUGAAAAUUGUUAUCUUCAUGAUUUCUUCCAAUGGGCUUAGAUUUGUUGGGACAGGGCAGAAUUAGAAUAAUUAUUUCUCACAUAUAAGAGUAAGUGAUAUGAGAUUGGGAAUUUCUUGCCAACACUCAAGCAAACUGCAGAAGAUAAUUACUCCAUUUUACUAGCUCACCUAGUUUCUGAAGGAUGGGGUGGGGAGUGAGACAUGGAGCCUCUGGGGACAAGGAUAGGGGGGUGGGACUGUCCCAGUGGAGGGUGCCACUGGAAGCCUCCACCCAAGUGGGCCAGCAGCUGUGCAAGGGUGCAGCAGUAGGCUGGUGAAAGCCAGGUUGUCCAGAUCUUUCUAGGGGAAGAGAAGGAUUAUAGAAAAGGAGAAAAGGGAGGAGCAAGAACAUCUCUCCAUGGCCUAUUUUUAUUUUUGUUCCCAAGAGACUAGUGUAAUAACCUUAUGCCCCCAAAGACAGCCCAGAACUGAGUAUCUUCAGUGUUCCUGAGUGUAAAUCAGUGAAUCUGUUAUAUAGAAAGUUAACAUUUCAGGAGCACAAUUAUUUCCUGAUUUCAAAUAUGAACAGAAGACUAAAUGUCAUUUUUUUAAAUCAUAAAUUUGGUAUCCAUAGUUACUUUACACAUUCCAGAGUCUAAGCAUGGAAUUUAAGUUUUGUAUUUUGAACAAAAAUAGCAACAUCUGUUUUCUGUAUGGCAAAGAAAAACUAAAUCCCAGACUUUUAUUUUUAACCACAGAAACCAUCACUUCUUUCUAAAUUAUUUGCUUGCCUGCUCAUUUCCCCUAAACAUCUCUGUUUAUGCCAAUGGCUUUUUAAAUCCAAAUAAUACUAGUUAUUGCCAAAUUGCAUUAGAAUCCUAUUGAAUUAGAAUAAUUCAUAUACUUCAUAUACUAGGCAGUAAAUGGUUAGAGACGGUAAAGAUCUGAUUGUGAUCAAAAGUAGGGUUUUUGUUUUGUUUUUAAUCAUGAGCACAUAUAAAAGGAAAUUCAAAUGAAACCAAGCCAAUUUCUGAUUUAGUAAGAUUAAAACCAUAGAUGGAGCUCAGUUAUUAAGGAUGGAAAGGAGGAAAGCACAGAGUGAGGAGAGAAAAAGGGGAAGGAAAAAAAGUAGUGUUUUUUUGGGGAACAGUAUAAUGUCUCAGAAGUUCUUCUCUCUUAUCCUGCUGAUGUUGAGACAGUGGCUUUGUAUAAGCUUUUAUUUAUACCUAUUUCAACAUCAUGAAAAUUUUUCCAUCAGCAUUUUCUUGCAACUUUAAAAAUCACAAGGGAUUAUUUGUUUAUAAAGAGAUACAGGAUCUAUAAUUUAUUGGCAAUACUUUAUUUUAGGAAUCUUCAAAUUGUACUUAAUAAAUAAAUCACAGGUCAAAAUGACUGUAAAAUCAAUCAGGCUUUCUCGUAAGUUAUUUCCUGAAAACCAUCCAUGAUAAAUACAACAAGGCUUGGCGAAACCUCAUUACUCUUGGAAGUCUUCAGAGGUUAUUAUACCUACUGAUCUGUAUUUGUCUCUAAGAGACAUUUGAAACACAGUUACAAUGUCAAUUUGGUGUAACAUUACCUGUAGUAGAGCUCAGAGUAUAUGGCAGUGCACGGUCACUCAAGAUGCAUGGCGUGUCAUUUGGGUCGCUUUGAUGGGUGCUCGGGUAGAAUUAGCCUUGUAGAGACUAAUGUGUUCAUGCUAUCUCUGAUCCUGUGGUGUUGUAUAAAAAUGAACAGCUAAAAAUUUACCCAUGACAAGAUUAAAGCAAAAAUAAACACAAAGUUGUUAGACUUUAAA